GUCUUCAACGCCUGCCCGGCCCGAGGACACCGUGGCUCUCGGAGGCGGCGGGCGCCGGGGGCUUCCCCCUGCUCUUUCCUCCUGCGGUGGGAGAGGCCAGGCCCACGGAAGCCCCCUGCGGCCCAGCCCACGCUCCCAGGGACCAGAGAGGACCGAGCGGAGGCGGCGGGAGUAUCCCCGGCGCAGCGACAGACGGUGGACGGACGGCGAGCGGCCCAUCAACUCCGCGCGCCCCUCCCCUCCGCGGCUGGCGCCUCCCAGCCCCGCCACCUCCUGCCCAGAGCUGGGGGCGGCGGGGUGAGCGCCAUGGCAGAGGCGGGUCGGGCUGCGAGCUCUGGAGAAAGGGGCGGCGGCCGCACGUGCGGAUCGGCCGCGCCCCACUGAGCAGAGAGCCCCCUUCUGCCGCCGACAGCCCGCGUCUGCACCGAGCCGGUCUCGGCCGGGCGCUGCCUUCACACGCGCCCAGGAGUGUCACGUGCGCCGCUCACCCCCGGGAAGGAAGCCCCUCGCCCACCCACUCCGCUCUACUCCACUCUUUCUGCAGACGUUAUUUUUGGCGGUAGGGCAGAGGUUGCGGCCCGAGGUCCGGGCGCAGGGACAACGGUCGCCAGCUCCUGCGCUAGUUCCGUUACUCUUCGGUGGCACACGGUCCUGGGCAGCGCGAGGCUCUUCCCGCCGUGGCCGCCGGGGAUUGGCUGCCGGCAAGCCCCGCCCCGUGCCCCCGGGCUCAGAGGGGGCGGAGCGCGGAGGGAGAAGGCGCGAAGGCUGGGCGUCGCGAUCGCAGGUGCACGCGCGUGGCCCGCGAGACGAGGAGAUCCUGUUGGAAAGCAACUGCAGCAUUCUGAGCUUGGGAGGUUCGAUGCUGACACCUGUGUUUGACAGGUCCUGGAACAUUAGUCACCCCCAACUCUCUGAUAAACUGUUUGGGAAGAAUGGAGUGUUGGAGGAGCAGAAAUCUCCAGGAUUCAAGAAAAGAGAGACAGAGGUGUAUGUUGGCAAUCUUCCACUGGAUAUUUCUAAGGCUGGUCCAACCUGUUACUUGACAGUGAAGUGGGCAGAGGAGCCCUACAUGUGGUUCCUGCAGUGGUCUGGGGAGGAGGAAAUUCUGUACCUUCUAAAGGACUUCAACCCUCUUGAUGUCCACAAAAUCCAGAAUGGCUGCAAAUGCUUUGCAUUUGUAGAUCUGGGCUCCAUGCAGAAAGUGACACUUGCAAUCCAGGAGCUGAAUGGUAAACUCUUCCACAAGCGAAAACUGUUCGUGAAUACAAGCAAAAGGCCCCCCAAGAGGACCCCUGAUAUGAUCCAGCAGCCUCGGGCCCCGCUGGUGUUGGAGAAGGCUUCUGGUGAAGGAUUUGGCAAAACCGCCGCUAUUAUACAGCUCGCUCCUAAAGCUCCUGUUGACCUGUGUGAGACAGAGAAACUGAGGGCAGCCUUCUUUGCAGUCCCGUUGGAAAUGAGAGGGUCCUUCCUGGUGCUGCUCCUGAGGGAAUGCUUCCGAGACCUGAGCUGGCUGGCACUCAUCCAUAGCGUCCGUGGGGAGGCGGGGCUGCUGGUGACGAGUAUCGUCCCGAAGACCCCGUUUUUCUGGGCUAUGCACGUCACUGAGGCUCUGCACCAGAACAUGCAGGCUCUGUUUAGCACCCUGGCUCAGGCGGAGGAGCAGCAGCCCUACCUGGAGGGCUCCACCGUUAUGCGCGGGACUCGCUGUCUGGCAGAGUACCACCUGGGGGAUUAUGGACACGCCUGGAACAGGUGUUGGGUGCUGGACAGGGUGGACACCUGGGCUGUGGUCAUGUUCAUUGAUUUUGGACAGUUGGCCACCAUCCCUGUGCAGUCUCUGCGCAGCCUAGACAGCGACGACUUCUGGACCAUCCCACCCCUGACUCAGCCAUUCAUGCUGGAGAAAGACAUUUUGAGUUCGUAUGAGGUUGUCCAUCGAAUCCUCAAAGGGAAAAUCACUGGUGCUUUGAACUCGGCGGUAACUGCUCCUGCAUCUAACUUGGCUGUUGUCCCUCCACUCCUGCCCUUGGGGUGUCUGCAGCAGGCUGCUGCCUAGGCCUGGACACAGUAUUUACCUGGCAUUCUUUUAGAUCAAACGAACUGGUUAUCUGAGGGGUUGGGUGAACUGGCUCGGGUGGGCCUUCCUUCCCACCAAGGCUUUGUCUUUCUCUUCCAGUUGCACAUCCUAAAGUUUGAAGAGUCUAAAUAACGGGGCUUCCCUCAGCAUGUUCCCUCUCCUGUUUGCCACGGAUCCAGAGGCCACCUGCCCUGUCUUCUCGUACCCCUUUCACUCUUGAGGCCUGGGAGGUGAAAAAGGCCAGACUGUGCCCAGGAUUGAUUCAAUUUUGCUUUUACUCCCAGCUUCCCUCUCAAAAGAGAGUGAAGUCUCAUUUGUCAUGUGUCUUCAGUUCCCCAACUUGGCAUGAACAUUUGAACCAAACAUAGGAAACUACCAUUAGGUUGAAAGCCUGAGGCAGCUGGGAUGGUCUUUCUUGUGUCUCUUCUUUGCACCCCAGAGCAUGAUAUAAGUGGUCCUAACAGAUUCUGGAUAAUGGAGAAGCCCUCUGCUGGUUUUCCUGGCAUUCCAUGUAGAAUAGGUAGAGAAUAUUUAACCAAUGAGCAAAUAAAUGUUGGCAUGUUUCAUGA